GGAUGUCCACGGUGGUCUCCGCGCCGGGGCGGGAGCCCAGGGGCUGUGCCGAGAGAACAUCUGGGCCUCAGAGACACCAGAACACCCAGCGGCCCGCGUCCAGGGAGUCUAGAACCUUGGGCUCCCGCGCACACCCAGGCCAGGUCCUGGCCGUCAUUCUCCCGCCGGCCUCUGGGGGAGCUGCGCGGUCCGCGCUCUCUCUCCGCUGCCGGAAUUCGUCUUGCCUGACGGAAGCUGGGGAGCGGGCAGGCGGCGGGGGCGGGGCCUGGAGGAGCCUACACCGACUCUGGAGGAAGACUGGAGCCUUUGCGGCGGCGCUGCCCCUCCCCUGGUCCCCGCGAGCUCGGAGGGCCCGGCUGGUGCUGCGGGGGCCCCGGGAGGUACGGACCUGGGAGGCGAGGCUCGUCCGGCGCUAGGAUCGGCCUCCGCCUCCGGGCCGCUUUAGGUUGAAAACUAAGCAUGGGGAAGAGCUGCAAGGUGGUCGUGUGUGGCCAGGCGUCUGUGGGCAAAACUUCAAUCCUGGAGCAGCUUCUGUAUGGGAACCAUGUAGUGGGUUCGGAGAUGAUCGAGACGCAGGAGGACAUCUACGUGGGCUCCAUUGAGACAGACCGGGGGGUGCGAGAGCAGGUGCGUUUCUAUGACACCCGGGGGCUCCGAGAUGGGGCCGAACUGCCCCGACACUGCUUCUCUUGCACUGAUGGCUACGUCCUGGUCUAUAGCACAGAUAGCAGAGAGUCUUUUCAGCGUGUGGAGCUGCUCAAGAAGGAGAUUGACAAAUCCAAGGACAAGAAGGAGGUCACCAUCGUGGUCCUUGGCAACAAGUGUGACUUACAGGAGCAGCGGCGUGUAGACCCAGAUGUGGCUCAGCACUGGGCCAAGUCAGAGAAGGUGAAGCUGUGGGAGGUGUCAGUGGCGGACCGGCGCUCCCUCCUGGAGCCCUUUGUCUACUUGGCCAGCAAGAUGACGCAACCCCAGAGCAAGUCUGCCUUCCCCCUCAGCCGGAAGAACAAGGGCAGCGGCUCCUUGGAUGGCUGAAGAGCUGCCGUUCCUCUUUCACGAUCCCAGCCCCAUUUCAGUGUCUGGGGCUCUGGUAGAUGUGUUGAGGGCAAAGUAGAGGACAAGCUGUCUUUCCCAGUCAGCCAGGGAGCUCCCCGCCAGGCCACGCCCCAGCCACUUUGCUCCCUCUCACCUCUGGGAAGUGCAAAUACUCUUGGUUGACAUCCCCUUCCUCAGCCCUCCCAGCCUACUCCCCAUCCCAGCUUUUAGAGGAUCUGCUCCACUGUCUCCUGGGGCAGUUGUGGGUCACUGUCCCUUCCAGCUGCCCCAGACAGGAAGCAGAGUCACCACGCAGCAGUGUCCCUUCUUGGGUCUGAGUUCCUAUUAUAGGUAGGGGCCCCACCCUCUGGGCUUCCCAUCAGCGACACACACACACUUAUGGCACCAGCCUGGACUCCAGAAAAAGGGUGUCCAGGUAUUGUGUGUAUGCAUUUAGUUGUGCACACACAAAUAUGCUCCUAUACUGGCAUUAGGCGUCUCCUCAUCCCUCACCCUGACCUUUCUCCUGUCCUUUUCUUGGCUGGAAGAAGUUGGCCUCCUGGGAGUGUAGUUUUCUGUUUUAAAUCCCCCACCCCUGGCUGGGCUCAGUGGCUCACCCCUGUAAUCCCAGCACUUUGGGAGGCCAAGGCGGGUCGAUUACUUGAGGUCAGGAGUUCACGACCAGCCUGGCCAACAUUGUGAAACCCCAUCUCUGCCAAAAAUACAAAAGUUAGCCGGGCGUAGUGGCACAUGCCUGUAAUCCCAGCUACCCGGGGAGGCUGAGGCAGGAGAAUUGCUUGAACUCAGAAGGCGGAGGCUGCAGUGAGCCGAGAUCGUGCCACUGCACUCCAGCCUGGUCAACAGAGCAAGACUCCAUCUCGAAGAAAAAAAAAAAAAAUUCCCCACCCCUACCAAUUGUUUUACUUCCUCUUCCUGCUCAGGGAGCAGAUGGGCCUCACUGGUUGAGAUGGAAUAGAAUAACUGGGCUAUGAGUCACCAGCCCACUUUGUGACCCAGCAAGACCUUUCCCCUCUCUGGGCAUCAGUUUCUCAUCUGUAAGAUGACCAGAGUUGCUUAGAUGAUCUCCUAGAUCCUUUCCAGUUCUCUUGAUUUCGUAAAGCCAAUGGCUUCUCCCUCUUUAAGGUGCUAUGCCAACCAGCCCUGGAGGCUGGGAUCUGCCGCUCCCUCCAGCCACCAGGGGGCAGGAGUGCACUACCUGCUGUCAGUCACCAGAGUGGCCGCUCAGUGCCCAGCCCGCCAGCCUCGCUCUUGGAGGCUGCUCUUUAUCCUGCCUGUGGUUUUCAGCUCAGAGCUGGACUUCUAUUUAUAAGUUACCUGUAUUUAUAUUUAUAUGCCCGCUCUCAUGGUGAAGGCUGGACAAGGUGCUCCUCUGGCCCCUCCUUCUUACCUCAGAUGCCUGAACAGAACAAGGCAAACCCGUAGCAGCCUCUCAGGAGCUGACAGGUCCUCUUUCGGGGCUCAGGAGGGUGGGCACACACCCAGCGGCCUGCAGAGUAAGCUUAUUACCCACAACUGUGCCCGCUUUGUGCUUCUAAGGUGCACACCUAGCCUAGGUGAGACACUGCAGCCAGGCAACCACCGACACACGCCCCUUCUCAAAGCCAGAGGUGAGUGGGGCAGGUGCCCGGGGCUGGGUGAGUGGAAUUAGGACACACACAGGCUUGGGCUUCAAGUUCAUUUAUUGAUGCAUUGGUUGGACACAAUAAAACCACAAUUGUUAUCAAAAA